CUGCGCGCUGGGGCUGAGCCGAGGGGAAAAACAAGCCCGGAGUCCGGGCUGCGGUCACAUGAUGGGGGGAAGGGAGGGGAACGCGAUGAAUGGCGAAAGAGGGUGGGGGAUGGACUUGGCGUGAACCGGGAGGCACCGCUCUGUGUGACCCAAAGAGGAGGCUUGGCAGGCGAUUCCAGUCUCCGCCUUUCAACCUAUGCUGCCACCGCAGGCCGAUUGAAACAAAACAAAACAAACCAGGCGAAGUGGACAGCCAGGUUUUUGUAGCUUUAAAUGCUGCGUGCUGUCUAGGGUGUUUCACUCUCCGCUGUGCACUCUACACUCGAGUUCAUUCUUAGGGAGUUUUCAGCUACAGUCGUUUUUAGAAGGAGCACUGACAGCGAGCUCUCGCCUUCAAAAAGAAAAUGAUCCCAUUUAGUCAUCAUAGUCCUGUUUUCCUCAUCCAUAAUAAUACUUUAUUCACAGAGUUGUUCUGAGUUUAAAAUAAAAUUAGAUGAAGUACAUGGAAGUGCUGUGUAGGAGUUUUGGGAUGGUGGUUGAUAACUAAGACAAAGUGCUGAAGAAAUGAUAGAAGUUGCAAAGAGACGUUAGUGUACUAUACUUGGUGAAUGUUGGAAACUGCAGGACCUGCUGUAGGGAAGAAAAAAGUUCUAGCUGGAAAGAAUGAGGAAACCAAAGAGCUCUGCAGAGGGAGGGGGAAGACAAGACAGACUGCAGCUGUGCUUCUGUGGACCCCAAGAACAGCACUGUUCAUACACAGAGGAUAGCUCUGAAGAGAGAUACCUGUGUAGUGCAGCUUCUAAAUUUCAUAAUAAAGUCAGAGCACCAUAACAUGGUGUGGGAAGUGAAGACAAAUCAGAUGCCUAAUGCAGUACAGAAACUCCUGUUGGUGAUGGACAAGAGAGCCUCAGGAAUGAAUGACUCAUUGGAGUUGCUGCAGUGUAAUGAGAAUUUGCCAUCUUCACCUGGAUAUAACUCCUGUGAUGAACACAUGGAGCUUGAUGACCUUCCUGAACUUCAGGCAGUUCAAAGUGAUCCUACCCAAUCUGGCAUGUACCAGCUGAGUUCAGAUGUUUCACAUCAAGAAUACCCAAGAUCAUCUUGGAACCAAAAUACCUCAGACAUACCAGAAACUACUUACCGUGAAAAUGAGGUGGACUGGCUAACAGAAUUGGCAAAUAUCGCGACCAGUCCACAAAGUCCACUGAUGCAGUGCUCAUUUUACAAUAGAUCAUCUCCUGUACACAUCAUAGCCACUAGCAAAAGUUUACAUUCCUAUGCACGCCCUCCACCAGUGUCCUCUUCUUCGAAGAGUGAACCAGCCUUCCCUCAUCACCAUUGGAAGGAGGAAACACCAGUAAGACACGAAAGGGCAAAUAGUGAGUCAGAAUCUGGCAUUUUCUGCAUGUCCUCCCUGUCAGAUGAUGAUGAUUUGGGAUGGUGCAAUUCCUGGCCUUCAACUGUCUGGCACUGUUUUUUGAAAGGCACACGACUGUGCUUUCAUAAGGGAAGCAAUAAGGAAUGGCAAGAUGUUGAAGAUUUUGCUAGAGCUGAAGGCUGUGAUAAUGAGGAAGAUCUUCAAAUGGGCAUUCACAAGGGCUAUGGUUCUGAUGGUCUAAAGUUGUUAUCACAUGAAGAAAGUGUAUCAUUUGGCGAGUCUGUACUGAAGUUGACUUUUGAUCCUGGUACAGUAGAAGAUGGUUUACUUACCGUAGAGUGUAAGCUGGACCACCCUUUCUAUGUUAAAAAUAAAGGUUGGUCAUCAUUUUAUCCAAGCUUGACUGUGGUACAGCAUGGCAUUCCAUGUUGUGAAGUUCAUAUUGGCGAUGUAUGUCUACCUCCUGGACACCCCGAUGCCAUUAAUUUUGAUGAUUCAGGUGUUUUUGAUACAUUUAAAAGCUAUGACUUCACACCUAUGGAUUCUUCUGCAGUUUAUGUGUUAAGUAGUAUGGCUCGCCAGCGUCGUGCAUCUUUGUCUUGUGGAGGACCUGGUGGUCAAGACUUUGCAAGAUCUGGAUUCAGUAAAAACUGUGGCUCACCUGGAUCAUCACAGCUCUCUUCCAAUUCUUUGUAUGCUAAAGCUGUCAAAAACCACAGCUCAGGGACUGUGAGUGCCACUUCUCCUAAUAAGUGCAAAAGACCAAUGAAUGCCUUCAUGCUUUUUGCCAAAAAAUACAGAGUUGAAUAUACUCAGAUGUAUCCAGGGAAAGAUAACAGAGCCAUAAGUGUGAUCCUUGGUGACAGGUGGAAGAAAAUGAAGAAUGAAGAGAGAAGAAUGUACACAUUAGAAGCAAAGGCUUUGGCUGAAGAACAGAAACGUUUAAAUCCUGACUGUUGGAAGAGGAAAAGAACCAAUUCAGGCUCACAACAACAUUAAACCAGGAUGCUUAUGUUCUUAAGUCUAUAUUUGCAUAUACAUUGACUCUUGAUGGAAAGACUUAAGAAGAUCAAGGUCUCACCAUUUGUCCUCAAUUCGUGUGACCAUAAGAUACUGAUAGCAUUGAGUCUUGAAAUGAUUUAAUAAUAUGAGUGAGGAUUUGCUUUCUCCAUUAGAGCAUUAAGCUAAAACUAUCAACAUUUUAAACCAAAUUGCCUUAUUUUUCUUCCAAACUUCAUAUAUGUCUAUCAGGUAAUAAUAGGCUUGAAAAUUGAUAUCCUGUGGUGCUAAAGUACAGUAGAAAGAGAGGAGAAGUGUAUACAUGUUUUAUUUUAAAUUGUACGAAAGGGGAAUUUAAAAAAUAUGUAACUGCUGUUUAUACAUUGGCUCCUUACUGCUUAUUAAUCUGUAUUGUACACAUGAUGAAAUGAAGCAGAAGCUGGGAGUCGGCCUUUCCUCUAGUAACCACCACAUGGCUCAGCAUCUGUGCCAAACAUAGGCGCUCCUAGUCUGGUCAGUGCCAAGAGGCUACCAGAACAUGGGGCAGGUGGCUGGUGUUGGUGUCCCAGCCUAAGAGCCACCUGCUGCAGUUACCAUGGCAUGCUGAGUUGAUGCACCAGGUGGCAGCAGCCAUCCGUUAUUAUUUCCAAUGGAGACCUAGCCCAGGCCAAGGUAAAGUUAGUUAAUAGCAUUGGGAUAUAGUCACUGUAAUGGUGCUAUUAACAAACAGUCAACACCAUUGUAUUUUUUAACUUCGUGUUCUGUAUCUCCUCAGCCAUGUAUCUUAAAUAUAUUUUGUCAUCAUAAUCUUUAUGGUGGGGGCAGACUUUGCACUUACUGCAGUGCAACACUUGCACUUUAAUUUUCCUCCAACUGUCUAAAAUUAGAGCAAAUACAUUGGCAAUACAGCUGCUUUUGCUCUGAGCUACAAUCAUGGCUUUUCAUGUUACUUACCAAGUGGUGUUUCUGGUUAGGAAUCACAGCUGUAAAAUUGAUUUCAGUUCAUCACACUUCUUCAUGAUGUUGCCCCUAAAUUUUGCACACUAUAUUCUUGUAUAUUAUUUCAAAUAAAUGGAAAAAAAAGUUGCUUA